AGAAGGGCGAGAGAAUUGGCAGGAUCCGUCUCCUACCUCUUCCUAGGCCCACAGCCAGUGCCUUUGGAGUACUGAGGCGCGCACAGAGUCCUUAGCCCGGCGCAGGGCGCGCAGCCCAGGCUGAGAUCCGCUGCUUCUGUGGAAGUGAGCAUGGUUGGGCAGCGGGUGCUGCUUCUAGUGGCCUUCCUUCUUUCUGGGGUCCUGCUCUCAGAGGCUGCCAAAAUCCUGACAAUAUCUACACUGGGUGGAAGCCAUUACCUACUGUUGGACCGGGUGUCUCAGAUUCUUCAAGAGCAUGGUCAUAAUGUGACUAUGCUUCAUCAGAGUGGAAAGUUUUUGAUCCCAGAUAUUAAAGAGGAGGAAAAAUCAUACCAAGUUAUCAGGUGGUUUUCACCUGAAGAUCAUCAAAAAAGAAUUAAGAAGCAUUUUGAUAGCUACAUAGAAACAGCAUUGGAUGGCAGAAAAGAAUCUGAAGCCCUUGUAAAGCUAAUGGAAAUAUUUGGGACUCAAUGUAGUUAUUUGCUAAGCAGAAAGGAUAUAAUGGAUUCCUUAAAGAAUGAGAACUAUGAUCUGGUAUUUGUUGAAGCAUUUGAUUUCUGUUCUUUCCUGAUUGCUGAGAAGCUUGUGAAACCAUUUGUGGCCAUUCUUCCCACCACAUUCGGCUCUUUGGAUUUUGGGCUACCAAGCCCCUUGUCUUAUGUUCCAGUAUUCCCUUCCUUGCUGACUGAUCACAUGGACUUCUGGGGCCGAGUGAAGAAUUUUCUGAUGUUCUUUAGUUUCUCCAGGAGCCAAUGGGACAUGCAGUCUACAUUUGACAACACCAUCAAGGAGCAUUUCCCAGAAGGCUCUAGGCCAGUUUUGUCUCAUCUUCUACUGAAAGCAGAGUUGUGGUUUGUUAACUCUGAUUUUGCCUUUGAUUUUGCCCGGCCCCUGCUUCCCAACACUGUUUAUAUUGGAGGCUUGAUGGAAAAACCUAUUAAACCAGUACCACAAGACUUGGACAACUUCAUUGCCAACUUUGGGGAUGCAGGGUUUGUCCUUGUGGCCUUUGGCUCCAUGUUGAACACCCAUCAGUCCCAGGAAGUCCUCAAGAAGAUGCACAAUGCCUUUGCCCACCUCCCUCAAGGAGUGAUAUGGACAUGUCAGAGUUCUCAUUGGCCCAGAGAUGUUCAUUUGGCCACAAAUGUGAAAAUUGUGGACUGGCUUCCUCAGAGUGACCUCCUGGCUCACCCCAGCAUCCGUCUUUUUGUCACUCAUGGUGGGCAGAACAGCGUAAUGGAGGCCAUCCGUCAUGGUGUGCCCAUGGUGGGAUUACCAGUCAAUGGAGACCAGCAUGGAAACAUGGUCCGAGUAGUAGCCAAAAAUUAUGGUGUCUCUAUCCGGUUGAAUCAGGUCACAGCCGACACACUGACACUUACAAUGAAACAAGUCAUAGAAGACAAGAGGUACAAGUCGGCAGUGGUGGCAGCCAGUGUCAUCCUGCACUCUCAGCCCCUGAGCCCCGCACAGCGGCUGGUGGGCUGGAUCGACCACAUCCUCCAGACUGGGGGAGCGACGCACCUCAAGCCCUAUGCCUUCCAGCAGCCUUGGCAUGAGCAGUACCUCAUUGAUGUCUUUGUGUUUCUGCUGGGGCUCACUCUGGGCACUAUGUGGCUUUGUGGGAAGCUGCUGGGUGUGGUGGCCAGGUGGCUGCGUGGGGCCAGGAAGGUGAAGAAGACAUGAGGCUAGGUGUAGCCUUGGGUGAGGGGAGGGCAUCCCUGGUCCUUUGAAGGUUCUCCCCACCCCAGCACACGCCACCCCUCUGUUCUCUCUUCAGCUCCACCUGCCACUGAUCCUGCAACUUGCUUCUUUCUAUUCUCUGCCUCUGUUUAGAAAUCUUCACGCACCACUGAGGCUUCUUGACUUGCCCCUUGUGACUUGAAACCCCAGCUCAGAUACAAAUUUUCACCUGCCAGCCCUGCCUCCUCCUUUCUCCCUUUUCCUAGACACAGGACUCUGACAACUUCAUCCUCCUUGUUUAGAUGACUUCCCAGUUUCCAGUCCCCAUUUCUCCUUCUAUCACUUUUCAUAAAAAAACUCAGGAAAUAUUUGACAUAUCUUCCAUUUCAAAUUCUUCCAUUUUAUGCAGAUAUCUUGCCCUUCCUAUAAGCUCUCCUCAAAGCUCAGGAAACCUGGUCUGCUCUCCUGCAUUUAGGGAAGGAGAACCCCUGCCAAGACCUUUGCUCACUGCCUGAGACCCCUUCCUUAGAGAGCACCUCCUUUGCUGGUCAGACAUGGAGCCUGCAGUUGGUCACAGAUGAUACUGCUUUAUUUCAGUUUUUACAGUUGUCUUCUUAAGAUUCCCGUCUUAUAAAUGGAGUACAGGGAACCUCAAGUAGUGAAGUGGAAAUCCAUGUGUAAGGCUUUGUGGCUUCAGGUACCAGUGGCUAAGGUAGUUUUAAAGACUUUGUUGAUUUUAGAAAAAGUCCAUCUUCCAUCCCCGACAUGGCAGUUAAUACCCUUCUAUAUGGUAAAACCUUAGAGAUUACCUUAAUCUGCUAGGAACAGAAGCAAGAAAAACCAUGGCGUAAACACCCCCAGAGUUUUUGUUCAUUUGUUUCAUCUUUCUUGAUAAAGCCCGAAGGUAGCCCAUUCAGGGCUGUUGUGGUUGGUUGCUCCAUCAUGUCAUCAAUAGCCCAUAUCUUUUCUUUUUUAUCUUCCUUAGUGUAACACCAAACUACCUCUCUGAUAGCUGGUGUUCAUGAAAUAUUUUACCUUCAAAUGAUUGUACCUUUUUAUUUGCUUUAGAGUUCUGAAAUAAAAUGAAAUUCCACUGUAAUAAAACUGUCAAAUGCAUGGUGUCUGAUGAGUUAAAAACACAGAGUAGAAAACAGGCAUAUGGAGAGGCCCUGGAUGAACCAUAGUUUUAGAUUGUUUAAUUCUAGAAUUGUGAAACAGAUCUUGAAACAAUUCAGAUCAAAAGAUGAAACUGUUACAAAUGCUCCUGCAGAAAUAGAGAAUGCCCCCCACCAAAAACUUUGCCAAUUCCAUGAAAGGAUUUGCUUGCGAGUCUGCAGAGCUGAGUGCUGGAUGUCUAUCCAUUUUGUGAGUUCUCAUGACACAAGAGCCAGAAGCAUGAAGCACGCAGAAGUACAUUAGAGUGUGUGUAUCUGUGUGCGUAUAAUACAAGGUUUUAUUGCUGUAAUUCUUAUGAAACCACAUGAAUUGAUUGAUGGCCAUACUCCCAUGAAGGGCAGACAUGGAUGCUUCCCUGUGUUUUCUGUUGAAUCAACAGCCAUGAUUUCAUUCCCCUCAUGAGCAACAUAAGGUCUUAGGGAUAAGCCUCCCUGGCCAGUAACUCCCCCCUCACCCCAGAACAUAGCCUUUCUCUAACACUUGGUAAUUCAUUGAGGUCAACUUUAUGCCACUUGUAUAAACUUGCAUCCCUAAAAUCUGAUCAUAAGCAGCCAAUGAGCCAGAAUGAUGCUUCUAAUCUUGCUCUGUCCAAGCACCCUCCACAGGGCUGCAAGCAUGGCUCUGACAACCUAGAAAUCUGGUGUUAUCCCUCACUGUUUAAAAUCUUUGUUCCCAUUGUGUGGAAUAUAAGGGCUCUAUGAUUUGGUCCUGGCUACCAAUCUAGGCACACCUGGAGCAGUUCUCCUCCCACUCUUUUCCAAAUGUUCGCUACACCCCCUCAGAACACAUUUUGCUGUUUUUAACCUCUGAGGUUUGUCUAUGCCCUUCCUUCUCUCAGAAAUACCAUCCUAUUCUUGCUGGAAUGAGAAACUUCUGCUUAUCUGUCAGUAUCCAGUGUCAUUGUGUUCACAUUGGUAAGCCUGUGCCUGACCACUACACCUGAAAUGGAGCUCACUGCAUUCUCUUUUGAAGCAUUUUUCUUACUAUAUCGCAAUUAUUUAUUACAAUAUCUGUUUCCUAUUUAGAAACCAUAAGGUCAUAAAGACAGGGACUGGUUCCUAUUUAUCUUGUUAUAGAACCUGGCAUAGUGCCUGGAACAAAUACUGCUAGGACAACUGGAUAAUAUUGAGAAAAAAGGCAAUAUUUGAUCCAGACUUCACACUAUAUCAAAAACUGAAUUCCUAUACACCAGAUAUCUAGGUACAAAAAAUGAUACCAUGCUGAGUCUAAGAGAAAAAGUGAAUUUUUCCAUAGCCUGUGUAUAGGGAGAGACUUUCUAAAUAGGAAGAAAAAAUCCUGAUACAACAAGAGAAGUGUAAAUUAAUUUGACACAAAAAACUUUGGCAUGGCAAAAAUCAUGGUAAGAAGAUUAGCGAUCCAAAUUAAAAAGUUGGAGAAACAUAGCUGCAGCAUAUAUCUUACACAUAGACCUAAUAUUUCUGAUAAACUAAGAACUAUUAAAAUUGAAGAAAGAACCUAUGAUACAUAUACAUACUGAAAUAAUAUUCAGCUUUAAACUACAAUAAACAAAAGCAGAAUAAGCUAAUAUGGAGCAAAUUCCAAUAUGGUUAAGUAAAAAAUAGCAAAGAGUAAGAGUAACUAUAGGAUGUAUCCUUUUUUUUAUAAGAAAAAGGAAAGUAUGUGUAUGGGGGAUAAUGAAAAAAAUACAUAUCUAUGUGCAUUGCCUUGCAAAAACAGUGCAGAGGGAAUAAACCAGAGUGUGAUAGAUUAUCUAUGAGGGUGGUGUUUGAAUAGGGUGGAAGGAUCCAUGUGUUUAUGUUUUUACAUAGUUUGGAUUUUGGAAACGUUAAUAUUUUGCAUACCAAGUAUAUGUUUAAAUAAACAAGGAGAGAAAAGCCAAGAACUGAAAUACAAACGGAAACAAAUGAAAUCAAUUUUUUCCAAAUGAAAAUGUAACUAUACUGUAGUGAAAAAAAUUAGCAUCAUUACCUUUUAAACACAGUACUUUUACUAUAUACUGUAUACAAUCAAUCAACAGAAAAAAAAAAGAACUCCAAACGAA